GGGGCUUCCCCAUCCCCCGAGGCUUCCCGGGAGGGCUGCGAGUCCGGGGAGCGUGCGGGGUCGCCACCAUCGGGACCCCCAGAGGAGAGAGGACUUGGGGCGGGAGCCGCGCGGGACGCUGUCCCCCUCCCGCCCCCCACCCCAUUUACAGAUUGGGAGACUGAGGCACAGGCCGCUGGCGGGCCCCGACGGCCACGGUUGGCCUCAGGAGCCCGGGGCUGUGAUUCCUACCGACCGCGCCGCGGGGCUUUCCCCCUUUCUAGGGUGAGGAUGGUUCUACACAGCCACCCGGAGUUCCUUAGUUGAAAGGUGCGCCCUGCUGUGACAGAAUGUGGUAAUUGUAAUCUUUAACAUUUUCAUGUAAAACAUAUUUCCUGAUCAUCUUUCCAUUGUCUUCAUGGAAAAUUGAUAAAUAUUUGUGCCUUCCAACUCUCGUCUUGGUUGAAUGACUUCAUCUUAAUACAACAUGGACACCACGUUGCUGAAAACAUGCUUUGGGACUGCCACUGAAUUUAUCUUUUGCGGUUUUAUGACAAAGUUAUUAGUAGUUUCCCUUUUUUGAAUUAGUAUUUUGAAGUUAAUAUCACAAUGAGUUCAGGCUUAUGGAGCCAAGAAAAAGUCACUUCACCCUACUGGGAAGAGCGGAUUUUUUACUUGCUUCUUCAAGAAUGCAGCGUUACAGACAAACAAACACAAAAGCUCCUUAAAGUACCGAAGGGAAGUAUAGGACAGUAUAUUCAAGAUCGUUCUGUGGGGCAUUCAAGGAUUCCUUCUGCAAAAGGCAAGAAAAAUCAGAUUGGAUUAAAAAUUCUAGAGCAACCUCAUGCAGUUCUCUUUGUUGAUGAAAAGGAUGUUGUAGAGAUAAAUGAAAAGUUCACAGAGUUACUUUUGGCAAUUACCAAUUGUGAGGAGAGGUUCAGCCUGUUUAAAAACAGAAACAGACUAAGUAAAGGCCUCCAAAUAGACGUGGGCUGUCCUGUGAAAGUACAGCUGAGAUCUGGGGAAGAAAAAUUUCCUGGAGUUGUACGCUUCAGAGGACCCCUGUUAGCAGAGAGGACAGUCUCCGGAAUAUUCUUUGGAGUUGAAUUGCUGGAAGAAGGUCGUGGUCAAGGUUUCACUGACGGGGUGUACCAAGGGAAACAGCUUUUUCAGUGUGAUGAAGAUUGUGGCGUGUUUGUUGCAUUGGACAAGCUAGAACUCAUAGAAGAUGAUGACACUGCAUUGGAAAGUGAUUACGCAGGUCCUGGGGACACAAUGCAGGUCGAACUUCCUCCUUUGGAAAUAAACUCCAGAGUUUCUUUGAAGGUUGGAGAAACAAUAGAAUCUGGAACAGUUAUAUUCUGUGAUGUUUUGCCAGGAAAAGAAAGCUUAGGAUAUUUUGUUGGUGUGGACAUGGAUAACCCUAUUGGCAACUGGGAUGGAAGAUUUGAUGGAGUGCAGCUUUGUAGUUUUGCGUGUGUUGAAAGUACAAUUCUAUUGCACAUCAAUGAUAUCAUCCCAGAGAGUGUGACGCAGGAAAGGAGGCCUCCCAAACUUGCCUUUAUGUCAAGAGGUGUUGGGGACAAAGGUUCAUCCAGUCAUAAUAAACCAAAGGCUACAGGAUCUACCUCAGACCCUGGAAAUAGAAACAGAUCUGAAUUAUUUUAUACCUUAAAUGGGUCUUCUGUUGACUCACAACCACAAUCCAAAUCAAAAAAUACAUGGUACAUUGAUGAAGUUGCAGAAGACCCUGCAAAAUCUCUUACAGAGAUAUCUACAGACUUUGACCGUUCUUCACCACCACUCCAGCCUCCUCCUGUGAACUCACUGACCACCGAGAACAGAUUCCACUCUUUACCAUUCAGUCUCACCAAGAUGCCCAAUACCAAUGGAAGUAUUGGCCACAGUCCACUUUCUCUGUCAGCCCAGUCUGUAAUGGAAGAGCUAAACACUGCACCCGUCCAAGAGAGUCCACCCUUGGCCAUGCCUCCUGGGAACUCACAUGGUCUAGAAGUGGGCUCAUUGGCUGAAGUUAAGGAGAACCCUCCUUUCUAUGGGGUAAUCCGUUGGAUCGGUCAGCCACCAGGACUGAAUGAAGUGCUCGCUGGACUGGAACUGGAAGAUGAGUGUGCAGGCUGUACGGAUGGAACCUUCAGAGGCACUCGGUAUUUCACCUGUGCCCUGAAGAAGGCGCUGUUUGUGAAACUGAAGAGCUGCAGGCCUGACUCUAGGUUUGCAUCAUUGCAGCCGGUUUCCAAUCAGAUUGAGCGCUGUAACUCUUUAGCAUUUGGAGGCUACUUAAGUGAAGUAGUAGAAGAAAAUACUCCACCAAAAAUGGAAAAAGAAGGCUUGGAGAUAAUGAUUGGGAAGAAGAAAGGCAUCCAGGGUCAUUACAAUUCUUGUUACUUAGACUCAACCUUAUUCUGCUUAUUUGCUUUUAGUUCUGUUCUGGACACUGUGUUACUUAGACCCAAAGAAAAGAACGAUGUAGAAUAUUAUAGUGAAACCCAAGAGCUACUGAGGACAGAAAUUGUUAAUCCUCUGAGAAUAUAUGGAUAUGUGUGUGCCACAAAAAUUAUGAAACUGAGGAAAAUACUUGAAAAGGUGGAGGCUGCAUCAGGAUUUACCUCUGAAGAAAAAGAUCCUGAGGAAUUCUUGAAUAUUCUGUUUCAUCAUAUUUUAAGGGUAGAACCUUUGCUAAAAAUAAGAUCAGCAGGUCAAAAGGUACAAGAUUGUUACUUCUAUCAAAUUUUUAUGGAAAAAAAUGAGAAAGUUGGCGUUCCCACAAUUCAGCAGUUGUUAGAAUGGUCUUUUAUCAACAGUAACCUGAAAUUUGCAGAGGCACCAUCAUGUCUGAUUAUUCAGAUGCCUCGAUUUGGAAAAGACUUUAAACUAUUUAAAAAAAUUUUUCCUUCUCUGGAAUUAAAUAUAACAGAUUUACUUGAAGACACUCCCAGACAGUGCCGGAUAUGUGGAGGGCUUGCAAUGUAUGAGUGUAGAGAAUGCUACGACGAUCCGGACAUCUCAGCUGGAAAAAUCAAGCAGUUUUGUAAAACCUGCAACACUCAAGUCCACCUUCAUCCGAAGAGGCUGAAUCAUAAAUAUAACCCAGUGUCACUUCCCAAAGACUUACCCGACUGGGACUGGAGACACGGCUGCAUCCCUUGCCAGAAUAUGGAGUUAUUUGCUGUUCUCUGCAUAGAAACAAGCCACUAUGUUGCUUUUGUGAAGUAUGGGAAGGACGAUUCUGCCUGGCUCUUCUUUGACAGCAUGGCCGAUCGGGAUGGUGGUCAGAAUGGCUUCAACAUUCCUCAAGUCACCCCAUGCCCAGAAGUAGGAGAGUACUUGAAGAUGUCUCUGGAAGACCUGCAUUCCUUGGACUCCAGGAGAAUCCAAGGCUGUGCACGAAGACUGCUUUGUGAUGCAUAUAUGUGCAUGUACCAGAGUCCAACAAUGAGUUUGUACAAAUAACUGGGGUCAUCGGGAAAGGCAAAGAAACUGAAGGCAGAGUCCUAACGUUGCAUCUUAUUCGAGCUGGCAGUUCUGUUCACGUCCAUUGCCGGCAAUGGAUGUCUUUGUGGUGAUGAUCCUUCAGAAAAGGAUGCCUCUGUUUAAAAACAAAUUGCUUUUGUGUCCCUGAAGUAUUUAAUAAGAAGCAUUUUGCACUCUAGAAAGUAUGUUUGUGUUGGUUUUUUAAGAAGUCUAAAUGAAGUUAUUAAUACCUGAAGCUUUAAGUUAAGUGCAUUGAUCAUAUGAUAUUUUUGGAAGCAUACAAUUUUAAUUGUGGAAGUUUAAAGCCUCUUUUAGUCCAUUGAGAAUGUAAAUAAAUGUGUCUUCUUUAUGGACCAAGGAUAUGAAAUCAUUUUUCUUUUGUAGCUAACGGUUGCCUUGAGGAAGAAAUAAUUUGGUUUUAUUAAGAGUCUACUCUCAAUCCAGUUAUUAGAGAUGUACUGAGUUUGAUUUGUUAAUCCUUUCUAUAUACUGCUGAUCUUGCAUGUCUACAAUCUGCUCAGUUUUUCUGUGUUUCUGCAAUAGUGGUCAGAAAAAUACUUAAAUUCCCUUAAUGGUGUUGUUUUCUAUUUGUUCUGGUUUUGAGAUAAAUGAGUGAUUCUGUCCCCAAAUGUCCAUUUUUGAAGUGAUUUUCCUGGAGGAUUAGGGUAUUUAGCAGUUGAAGCUCUUCAUUCAUAGUAGUUACUGUCAGCUAACAGGUUUUUUAAGGCUUUUAACUAUUAAUAUUUUAUGGAAUGGGGCAAAGUAAAUUGAUGAAAGAAUUGGAGUGAUAAUAGUCCUUUACAAACAUACAGUCCAUAAGAAAAUGAAUUUGGCAUAUAGAAUUAUUACAAUUUCCUGGGAGAGAUGGAUAUUUAAACCUCUAUUAUUUUAGACAAGACUGUCUAGAACUUAAGUUUGAUCUGUCAGCCAGUACUCCCAUUAAAUUCAGUGUAGUUUCACUUGAUAGAAUCAGAUAUGUUAUCGAAAUGUUAGCAGCAGCUUCAUCCUCCUUCUGAUUAAAGUAAGUAGAAAUGGGAUGUUUUGUUUAAUAACAGCCAUAGUGUGUGUUUAGACCACAGCGGAUGUUGUAGACCAGGACCAUAGAUGAUACAUGUCAGUGCUGUGGAAUGUGCAUUCUCUGAGUGUUGUUUUGUGGUAUCAUUGUCUUUCCUGAAUGACUUUCUAACUGUGCAGAAAGGCAGAAAAGUCAUCAUAUGUAUAUGUCAUAUGACUUUAUAAAAUAUUUAAUGUGACAAAAAGUGGAAAGAAUCUUUACAAACCCUGCAAUUACUUUUUUAAAGGCACUUUUACUCUUUGGUUUUAUCAUUCCAUUUUGCUAAUAUUUACUAGCUUUAUAAAUUACAGUAAGGUACAAAAACUCAUCUUGUAAUAUUUUCAUUUUUGAAGUGAAAAAGUACAUAUAUUUUGCACAAGGUUUUAUACUGCUAAGUGCUUGGUUGGGGUGGUGAGAUGAUGAUUAGAUCAGGGGUGAGGCUGAGAGACUCUGGGUUUAGGGCUAGCCCUGCCUCCAUCUCCCUUGGGUAAAAUGAAGGGUGUGGGGUAAAAGAUGCAUAAGGCCUUUUCUAGCUCUGACAGCCUAGAAGUCCAAUCACCCUGUAAUAAAUAUGUGUUGAAUGAAGAAAUGGGUGAAUGAGCUUGUCAAUGUGAUUUUAAAAAAUUGACUACCUGGAGGAAUGAUUAGGAAUCUAAAUGAAGCCAGCCCUCGGUAUCUGCAGGUUUCUCAUCCAUGGAUUCAACCAACUGCAAAUGGAAAAUACGAUUUUUUUUAAAAAAAGGAUGGUUACAUCCGUAUUGAACAUGUACAGACUUUUUUCUUGUCAUUAUUCUCUGAACAAUACAAGAACUCUUUAUGUAGCAUUUACAUUUAUUAGGUAUUAUAAGUAAUCUAGAGAUUAUUUAAUUAAAAUAUACAGGAGGAUGUGUGUCAGUUAUAUGCAAAUUCUGUACCAUUUUGUAUCAGGGAAUUGAGCAUCUUCAGAUGUUGGUAUCUGCAGGGAUCCUGGAACCAAACCCCUGCAGAUACUAAGGGCUGACGAUCUAGGUAAGACUGGAUUUAACAGUUGGAAAAAAAAAAAAAAAAGGAGAGAGAAGACAGUUCCUUUCCUGUAGAAAUUAAAACAAAAUACAAAUUGAGGAAGCUCUGCUACCCAGGCUGUCAUGGUAGAGAACUUGAAGAAGACCUGUUUGGAUGGACACCUGGUUUCAAAAGUCAGGUGUGGAGACUGUUAAAUGGGAGGGCCUCAUCCAUAAAUGAUUUCUGGCAACGUCUUCUUCAGGUGGAGCUUGACGUCUUUUUAAUGUUACUUGGGGAGGGAGUGCUCAUUAAGGGAUGCCAGGGCCAGCUCUGGUGGUUCCUGGGGAGGCUGCGUCCUUCCCUGCUUCUGCAUGUCAUGAGGCAGCAGGAAGGUUUCCCCUGCACCUGUCUGUCCUGGCUCCCUCUGGGUAGCCCCCUACUGUUCUGUGCUUCAGCACAGCCUGGUUUGUCAAGAGGCACAUAGUUGGGGCUGGGCUGCAUGGCACAGGGGCUUAUGUGCCUGCUGGUUAUUUAAUUUUCAGCCUUAAGUUUUCUUUAAUAUUUUCCUGUUGGCUAUUUAAAGGUUUUGGUUAUCUUUUAUUCCUUAUCUACAAUCAAGAUGACAAUGUAAUUGAAUUAUCUUAUUUAUAACACGGUUCGUGAUUCAUGAUUCAUGAUUACAAGUAGAAAAUAUGUCAUGUUCCUCACCUCCAAAUAAAUAUGUGUGUGUCUGUGUGUGUGUAUAUAUGUAUGUGGCGGAGAGGGAGAGAGUGGGGAAGGAGAGCAGUGUUAUCAUACAUAGAGAGGCUAAAUGUGUCCCAUCCCUCACUGUCAGCUUUAUAAAGGAGUUUGACUCCAUCCACAGAAGAAUGUUUUAUAAGACUAGGAAAACACGUUGAAAACUAGGAUAAACAGCAACAAAAAUCAACUAAAUAUGUUGUUACUGUUGCUAAGGAUUUUCUCCUUAGAAUAAUUUAGGAUUUUUAAAAAUUUCUGUUUGCCAAAUGCUGUAGAUAAAUGGCCAGAUUCUUCCUAUCCCUAGGAUUCCUUUAUUAUUUUUUUUCACAGAUUUUGAGAACAAGGGGGAGAGAUAGUAUGGAAGAUUAAGAUUCCAUUAAUCUUAUAGAACUGUGUUGUCACCCAAAUUCCUGCUUGUUUGAACAUGGCAUCUUCAUAGAUUCAGGAUUCACUACCCUCUAUAGCUGGAUCUUGAAAAUUAUCUGGCCAGAUAAUUUUGCAUCUGCUUGGAUGAUUGUAGACUGAGAUGUGAGUGGAGGAUAAAGUAUUAGACUUUUGCUGAGUAACUGCCAACCAAGAAGUAUUUAUCGGACACUUACUAGGUGCCUAGGAUUGUAUCAGAGGGAAUAUGAAAUGUGUCCCUGCCCUACCUAGUUUUAACGACAGAAUAUCUAUUAAAGGCUACUUAGCUGAAGGGUAAGGGUGACAGGUCUAGGGGAAGCUUUGGGAGGUGGUGUGCUGUGACAGAAAAAGUGGCAGAGUAGGGACGAGAGACCUGCAUUCUAGCCCUGUUUCUGUCACUUGCUCUGUACACUUAGACAACAGCUUGACCUCUUGAGCUUUAGUUUCCUCCUCUGCAUAAUGAGAGGGUUAGACUACUGAAUUGUAUGGGAAAAAAAUACAAAUUCCUGGGUCCUAGGCCAUGCCUGCUGAAUCCGACUGUUCAGGAAGAGGCCUAGGAAAUCUGUGAGGGAAUCCCCAGGGGAAUCUCGUGACCAGCCAGGUGUGAAAUCUGCUAACUGGAAGAUCUCAAAGCUUCCUUCACUUUUUGUGAUUUUGUGGUCAUGUAACGUUACUGUAUUAUUCUACGUAAAUGUGGGUACUUGGAUGUUUAUCAUACUGUUUCUCUGUGUUUACAUACUAAUUUGUGUAAGAAAUGCAUUUUAGUCUGUGUACCUCAACCUGCUGUUUGUUUCCUAGAGGUGUUAGUAGUCUUUAAAUACAAGUAAGACUUAAGAGGAUAUUUGAUGUUAUUUACCUGGAUAUUUUCUUCCCCUUUUAUUUAUUUAGAGGAAAUUGAGAUUCUAGGAGCCAAAAAAAUGAAAACAAAAUUCUAAGGCAAAGUUAAAGAAAAAAAUUACAUUAUUUCUUACCAUUUGCUACUUUAUAAUGAAAAUUUAAAAAUUAUAUGGGAAGAUUUUUCUCUGGGAUAACAAAUCCUUGUCAUAAAGUAAGAGGUCUUUUUAAAGUAGGUAGGCUAUAAGGCCUGUAAUUUAAAAUAAUACUCCUUUCUCUAGGGUUUGGUGCAAUUCUCCAUUAAUGAAGAUAACAUUUGAAUUCCCCAAAGCAGGUGAGGAGUCGGGGAGGAGAAAGCGAUGUUAAAAUGAAAACUCACUGCAAAAGAGGAGGCAGAGGAAGAAGGAAUGUAAACCCCUUAAAGCAGAUGUGUGUGGGGCCUUAUGAAGACCAGGAUUCUGCGGGUGUCAGGGGAUUGCCCCUCUUGACAGAGACUAGGGUUUUAGACUGAGGCUUCCUGCAGGGUGUUCGCAUUGCCCUUCUCCGUUCCCCUUCAGACCUUUCUGGGGAGAAGAGGUGGGAGGAGGGGAGAAAGACUGUUCAUCUUAUUCUGAAUCCUGGAGCAGCUGAAGGUUUUCUCUUGAGUCAGGAUGCAGUGGUAAUGCAUUAACCAGCAAGUGUGGCCAAGGAUAAUGAAAAAGUGGGAAAGGAAGGUCCUCCUCCUCCCUGAUUGUAGCAUCCAGCAGUCUCUGUAGCCAGGUUACUCAAGAACCACAUUUGAUUUCCUGGCCCUUUGCCUUGGCAGUGAUGGCAUUUUUAUUUCACUGUGUUUUAAAGUCUUCAUUUAUUUUUAUAACAUGGGUUAGGGAGAAGGGCCACAAAUGGAGGGAUUGUCCUUUCAAGCACCACAGCUUCAGAUAAAAUUAGUACUUUCAAAUAUUGUCCACUUUAACUUAAAAAAUUCUAGAGGGAUUAUAUUGGAGACUCAACUGCCCUUGGUUUUAGUUUAUAAAAUGGCCUAGUACUGUGGAAUUUUAAUUUUAGAAAGUCUUAGCAUCAGAUCAUAAACAUUCAUUAAAAGAACUCACAUCCCAUCUGAAACUUCCCAGGGGAGUUGGGAUUCUUAGUAGAUUGGUAGAAAGGGGCUCAUUUUCUACUGCAUUUCCCAUUUUUGGUAUCUUGUUCAGCAUGUUUUAUUUUUAUUUCUUGUCUGCAGAACAUCCUAUAUUUAUGAGAACAUUCUUUAAGAAGACCACCACAUAGAAUACCCCUUCCUAUCAGCUCGCUCUGAUUUAGCCUUAAUUUUGUUAAAUUUUUUAGAGAUGAAUGAAGUGCUGCUGUGGAAAGAAAUGUACAUAUACUAUUUCUGUAUCAUUAAAAUUACAUUUUUAUGGUUC